AGUGCAGGAGCGACCGGUGGGAGCUGGCCGCCACUGGGGGCCCGGGGCGCGCCCGCGAGGGAAUGGAGAGCCAGGGGCGGCUUCGGAACCCAGGGCUGGCGGGUUUGGCAGCCUCCGCGCUCGUGGCCGUGCGCGCGAGGAAUCUGGGAGAAAUGGGCACCUUCCACGGCUGCCUGGCCCGCACACCUGGCGGGGCCGGCGAGUUGAGAUGCCCCCGCCGGCUGGCGGAACUGUGCGCCCCGCCCGCCGAGGCCCGCUCCCCCUCGAGGCCUGAGGCCCAGUUCUAUAGGGGCGCGAGAGAGCGGCGGCGUGGGGGGCGCGGAGGAAGCGCCGGCCCCCGCCUCCACCGCCUCCUUCGUGGUUGCGGCCCAGGCCGAACAGGGUACCGUGCCCCGGCCGCCUUGGCCUUGGCCACCGCGAGGUCCGGGGCGACUACACCCAGCAGCCCUGUGGCCCUCCUACUGCUCUGGAGACCUGGAGUGGGGUUACAGAGGGAAGCGACUCGCUGCGAGCUCCCCAUCGAAUAUGGAGCCACCAGGUCACGGGACGACGUGCGCUCUACAGAAUGUGAGACAAGGGCCCUCCACACCCAGCCAUUCAGGCCUGAGGUCCUGGCUCCGAGACUGAGGCCGAGACGCGGCAAGCCCCGCGCCGGACCAGCUCUGCCCCUCCCGCACCCACGUGUCUGCGCACAGCCCUCCUUUGCGAUAGAACCCCCUUCCUGGUUCUCCACCACUAAUGAUCUGCCGGAAUUAAACUGGUAACUUUCCCUGCCCUUGAACCGGGAGUUUCGGGAUGAGUUUGCCAAUCCCUGUGCUAUUUGUAACCAGCCCCGUGACACGUGAUACGGAUCCAACUGUGCUAGUUUCCACACCAGGGGUCAGGGCACGGUGGAAGGUGAGUCAAGGGUUCUCUGCCCAAGCGCAGAGGUGCCCUGAGCCACGGGGACUUCCCAGCCCUGCCUUCUCUUCUCAGCUUCCUGUCUGCCUUGCCUGAAACCCUAUCUAGAGUUAAGGCCAAUGGAUGAAACUUUUCAAUGUGCAAGCAAGCACUUUACCUACCUGAUACAACAAGAGAUUCCUGGUCAUGCUCACUGAAGGUAAAGUAUGAAGCAGGCUUAGCUAAUCAUCAGAGGUGAGAAGAGACUUAAAGAACCAGUCAGAGAGGUAAAGAGGGGAGGGGGUUACCUGGGCUUUAGGGUUCACCAGGGAGGCAGAACGGACAAGUUCUUGCCAUUGGAAUUUGGUGGGGCACUUGCCUGGGUGGCCAAAGGUGGACUUUUUCAUAGCCAGGGUGCCCGACCUCUGUAAAUCCCCGCCAUAACUAACAGCCCUGAUUACUGUCGAAAUGAACAAUGCCAACACUCACGACCCCUUGCUUUGUGGUUCUUUGCUACAUCUCUCCAGCAGUUCAGAAAAGGUUGGAGGCAGCAGGGGACAGGAGACUGAGAAAAACAGUCAUUUGUCAGUUGAGGAAACUGAGGUCCAGGCUGACAGAGGUAAAGUAACCUCUGCAGCUGGUUGACAUGCAGAGAAGGCCUGAGCCAGAUGCAGAUGCGCUGACCAUUCAGUGUUUCUCCCGCAGCACACCUGUCACUCAGAGAACACACCAUGCUGUGAACCCAGAAAACGCCCUCAUGGCCUUGUGAUGCCAAGCACGUUUAGAUUAUUAUAACAAUACAGGCACUGUGUCCCAAGGACAUUGCAGUAAUCUAUGUUUGGGGUGGAGAUAUCCUUCCUGGUCCAAGUGUCAAGGUAUACCACCUUCUGGAAGGGCACCAAAGCAUGUCCAGCGAAUGGGCAGAUACCCAAGAGUGGAUUGUACAACAGCAGGCACUGGCUUUCUAAGAACUCAGGCCCUCAUUAUAGGAUUUGUCCCCUCUGACACAGGCCUGUGAACAACUCUUCAUUGUGCAAAAGGGUUUCCUUGUCCUUUCCCUACUCAUUCUUCCCUUCCCCCUUAUUUGAAACUGAAUCUCUGGCCAUGUCAUGUGCAGGCCUGCAAGGGGCCUGUUGAUACAGCUGCCCCUCUGGUGCCACAUGACUGCAGGCUCACCACCCAUGACAGACUUGAAUAUCCUGGCACCAAGGACAAUCAGAUUAGCCUCCACUUGGUAUAUCUGCUGUUCUCACUGUUUGUGUCUAUGAGAGCCUGUUUGACUAAAUUAAACUCCUUGGAAAUUGAUCAUCGAUUAUGUAUGAAAGACAUACCCACCAGCCUUUGAGGUACUUAUCUUUGUAGCCCACCUAGCCUUAGGAGAGAAGCUGCGUGGCCUGGUCACUAUCUAGUGGUCUUCCCUGGCCUGUGUGGUAGUGAAAAAGAUAAAAGCCAGACCGAAUCCUUAGAAAAACAGCAUCAGAACAAGAUUAAAAACCUCGAAUUCAGUGACUGUAGAAGCAUAAAGCAGAGGCAUGUGUUCAUGUAUUUAGCCAGCACAGAUUUACCAACUACCAAUAAAACACGGAACUUGUAUUUUAUUGAGGAGAAAGGCAAUAAAAUAUGUAAGUUAUACAGAGAAUUAGAAAGUGAUUGAGUGCCAGGGAGAACAAUAAAUCACAGAUGGGGACUGGGGAGCACCCCAUUUUAAAUAGGGGAGUUAAGGAAGGCAUCUCUGAGAAGGUGAGAUUGCAGCAAAAACUUGAAGGGAAUGAGGAAGCAAGUGUAUCAAUGAUCUAUUAUUGCAUAACAACUUACCCCAAAACUUUGAAGUUUGAAACAGCAAAAAUGUAUUCUCAGGGUUUCUGAUCAGGGUCAGAAACUGCAAGUGGCUUAGCUGGGUACUUCUGGCUGAGCCUCUCAGAGGCUGCAGUCUAGCAGUUGGCCAGGGCUGUGGUCAUCUGAAGGCUGGACUGGGGCUGGAGGAUCUGCUGCCAAGGUGGCACAUUCACAGGGCUAUUGGCAGGAGGCCUCAGUUCCUCACUAUGUGGAUUUCUCCACCCAGCCUCCCCUCACGUGAGUGAUCCAAGGGAGAGCAAACAAAGGGGAAGCUGUGGUGCCUUUUCUGACGAGGCUCUGCACUUCCAUACCAUCACUUCUCUUUAUUCUGGUCCUUAGAAUUGAGUCACAAAGUCAAGGGGAAUGGGAUUAGGUGCCACCUCUUGUAGGGAAGAGUAAGAAUUUGUAAGCAUAGUUCGUGAUUUUUUGUGGGAAGUAGGGAAGAGUGCUUCAGGCAGAAGUAACCACAGGUGCAAAGGCCCUGAGGUAGGAACACACAUAUUAGCAUAUUCAAAGGAGAGCAAGAGGCCAGGGUGGCUGCAGUUGGUGAGCAAGGGGGAGAGUAGGAGAGGAGGUCAGAGAGGAAAGGCAUGUGCAGGGCCAAGGGCACCAGGUUGUGCAGGGCCUUUAAGUAGGUGGGAAGCCUUUGAAUGGUUUUUGAGCUGAUGUGAUGAGCUUUGACAGUGAUGUGAUCUGAUUUCUUUUAAAAAAGAAAUUGGUGGCUGUUGCAGUAAGAAUAGCCCAAGGAGGAGCCAGGAUGGAUGGGAAGAGGCCAGUUAGGAGGCUGUGGUAACAACCCAGGAGUUAUGUCUGUAGCUUGUGUAUGAAGGUGAUGAAAGGGAUGAGACUUUGGAUAUAUCUUGAAGAUAGAGUCAAUGGGAUUUUCCAUGAACCACAUGUGGGUUUUGAUUCCAAGGUUUUGGAUCUGAGCAAGUGGAAGAAUGGUUCUGGCAUGAGCAAGAUGGGGAAUCCUAAGAGUGGGACAAGUUUGAGAGGAGGAGCUUCAGAGUCCAUUUGGGGACAUGUUAAUUUUGUCCAUUAGACAUCCGAGUAGAGAAGCUGAGUAGGCAAUUGAAUAUGGAGGCUUGGAGUUCAGGAAUUCGGAAGGAAUACUUUCCUGUGGUCUGUGAGUGACAUUACAAAAUUGAGGAGGCUGGGCUCCCUCUCUGGAAGAGUAACAAUUAGUCCUUUGGAGGGUUCUAAACACACAAAGCAAGGGAGGGGCUGGUGCCAACCAAGUGCAGUUUUCAGAUGUUUCUGGGGUGCAGAGCACAGCUAGUGCGGCUGGGAGGCAUGAGUUUCACCCAGAGCAGGGGGCUUCUGCUGCUCUGUUCCCAAAACAGUGCCCUAAGGAACACAUAUCUUUCACUUCAACAAGACAGGCCACGUAUUUCUUCCCAGGGCACUGCCAACCCUGAGAAGAAACUCAGGGCAAGUGGAUUGACCUGCAGAAUUCAGUGGCACCAUUUUUCAGAAUUCAUAAGAUGGCAGAAAGACAAUCAGCUAAUCAAGUCUGCCAACUUCUAGGUCUCUUUUCUCUUUUGGUCUCUUUCUAAUUCUGCCCCAAAUUAAUCUUAGCACCCAGAAGCACACAUUUCCCUGCUUCCAAUUUCUGAUGUUUUCUGAGCCCCAGCUGGGCUUGGUUUAUAGGAAUUUAUUCUUGAGCGCUCAGUCUUGGGUCCAUGUUUCAACACAUAUUUCCAGGACUCCCAAUGACUCCUCUGAACCAACCUGGGCCCCAUCCAGCUGUAUAACCCUGAAAAGGGUGUACCAAAGUCCCUGGGAUAUUUUCCUCCUCCCUAACCCCCAGGUCGGACUUAGACCCAGGGGCUUCAGAGACAUAUCAGGAGUGCAAGUAGAGGCUGACUAAUUUGGAAAGCUUGAAUUAAGGGUUUAGACUGGCUCCCUUAGCUGAUCCUAGUGCAAAGGCUAAUCUUUUGCAGAGUCAUUUUAUGGCGUGAGAUGGUGCUGUUGAUUUUGCACAGUUAAUAACAGCUCAGCCUGAGUGCUGCUAGCCUUAGCCAAGGGUGUAGAAUGCAAGCAGUUGUUUCAGCGAAAGUAAGAAUUUGCUGGGAGCACACUUGGCUUUUCUGAAGAGGCCUCUGCACUGCCAAGGGAGAAAGACCCCCCCUCAACAGUGGCCACAGCAUCUGGUCUGUGGCUAGAGGAGACCAACGUGUUGAUAUUAAGAGUUCUUUGGAAAAGUACUGUCUCUUCACUCAUUCACUGCUGACUGGAUCCCAAAGAAUGCACUGUCUCCCCAGCAUGCAGAAAGGGGAUGAAUCAAACUGAGUUUAGAUCCUGGCUUUGUCACUUACCAGCUGUGUGACCUGGGGCAAGUAAACAUCUUUUCUGUAUCUUAGUGUUCUCAUCUGUAAUGUGAGAAUAACCAGACCUACCUCGAAGGAUGUCUUGCUUGAAGAGUAAAUAUCUGGCACAUGGAGAGUGAUCAAUAAAUGGAUUUCUCCUUAACUACUACUCGUCUAGCUACACUCAUCUCAUCUUCCACCUGUGGCUCAGGAAGCUUGAGCUGAUGAAUCCAUGGAGACUGUAAAGAAAUAGCAGGGGAGGUCGAUCAGGGUGCUCACUGAGAGCAAACUGUGGCUCUGUUGAUUUCUGAUGCCCAGUUGGCAAUGGUUGGAGUUCCCAGCCUGCCAGCUCAGCUGUUUCUCCCUAUAGCGCAUCUCUCAGUUAUUUCUAGGAGUUCUUAAAGGUGUGCAUCGCAUCAUCUCAAAAACCAGCCCGUCCAACUUGUGUUAUCUGCCCUGUUGAUCUACCUUUGUUUUCCCAAGGUCUGCAGCCUCCAAAGCUUCUGAAAUGGGACUUGCUGCUGCUGGUAUCUUUAGAGGGGCAUGUGGUAUCCUGCCAAGGGUGAUUCCUUAGCCUGUCAGUGGCCCAGGGCUCAGGAUUCUACCUGCCUCACAUCUCCUGGAUCCAUCUGCAUGUCUUGGCCCAAUCUCCAUAUCCUCGGUUCUGGCCCCUCCACUACCUGGUUGCCACUGAUGAUUCCAAGGAUUCAGAUCAGCUCACAGUGCUCCAAAAAUAUAGCAAAGUGAAACAAAUGUGCAAAUAAAUGAUAAAAACAAAAGAAGAAAAAGAAAGAAAAGACUUAUUGUAUAUCCUACCUCCUUCAAACAGCUUGCUGUGAUGUGCAUGGUGGUGUGGGAACCUUCUGAUGUCAUACAUACAGGUUUCCUUCGCCUUCUGUCUUGAUUGGAAACAGCCUGAAGCCCUCACCAGAAGCCAGAGGCAGAUGCUGGUGCCAUGCUUCUUGUACAGUCUGCAGAACUGUGAGCCAAAUAAACCUCUUUUCUUUAUAAA